AGUCCGGACUUUAUUACAAGCAGGACUACAGUGAUGUGUUUUCAGCACUGAAGUGAACUCCAGUGUAAGUACAGAAAGUGGCUUCUCUGCUUUCCCUCCGAAGCACAAGCAUAUACACGUUGCAGACUUGGUAAGUUUUCUUUGAAUGAUCUUUUGAUAAAUAUGUAAAAUUAUCUUACUGUUUGGUCUUGCCUGUAAAGGCUGAUGUAUCGUUUUAAUAACUUUCAAACUGAGAGCAAAAUCAGACUUCAUGUGAAACAAAUGGUUUUGCAGUGAUGAAAUGCUUGUUUUAAUAGGCAUAUUUUAGUUUACUAUUGAUAGAAUUUGAUUGUUUCUGUUACAUUAUUAUUAUUAUAGAAUUCUAAUUUAGAUUAUGUCUUUUCUGUUGUCUUUUUAAGAAUUGUAUCAUUUCUAGUGUUUCUGAGGCAUUACUUUGCAGACUUGCUAGCAGCGCCAAGUAAAUGAAAAUCUAUCUGCCAAAAACAUUCUGUAAAAUCUUUGGAGCAAAAUUUUUGAGAAACAUUAGUGUGUCUUCCUUCCCAAGUCCCUUUUCCCCUGCCUCAAAUAAUGUUUGGGCACAAACUUUUUUUCAGAAUAUUAGCCCAGUUUGUUUCUUGUGUACUUUUCAAGGAAGACCAGUUCUGAAUGGUGGAUGGUGUAGUUAAUUGGUUUUCAUCUACCAAGAAUGUGAAUUCCAAUGCUCCUGGUUUUCAGCUAAUGCAGAAUGCAGUAGCAUAUUUGAUGGUUCAUUUGAUAUAUUUUGUUUCCAAGUAAAGUCGUGUUGUAAAUAGUGCACAGUCUUUUCCGUCCUACUCCCAUGUAGCCCUCUACCAAGUUCUCCUCACAAUACAGUGUGUUCAGAAAAUAAAGAAGCCUUUUUGAAGAUAUGUUUAGCUUUUUUCCACCUUAAUCCUGGGCAUUUCUCCUACUACUAUGGCCAGAUUGAAAGGACCCUUGAAUGAAUUGGAGUAAACACUGCAGUUUGUGCCUGUCCGCAUUCACAGCUGUUUAGUCGCUUUGCUGUGCGGUAUAUUUUGAUGGCCAGAGAGAAUAAAAAAACUAGCCCAAAGAACAUUUUGUUCUGCUGUAUAUCUGUUGGAAUGUGAGUAGGGACUCCAGUGCUUAAGAGCCACUGAUGUGCCUUUCAUCUUACUCGAGAAAAAAUAUAUGGGUUAUAUUACUGAACUUAGCUUACAUAUUUUGUUUAUGUUUUGUUACUUGGAACUGUGAGGCCAAUUUUAUUUUUAUGUUACCCUAAUACAAACAGAGAAUUUGGACGCUGACAUAGAGCUUGCUUUUCAGCUAUUCUUGUUGUAGACCAGCUCACUUCUUGUUAUUUAUGUGAGCCUGGGCAAUGAUCUUGACUUAAGCCUUGGGGGUCUUUGUCUGUAAAAUGGGUAUAAUAACAGAAAUUAUGUCUUACCAUUGUUGUGGGAUUAAAUGAGAUAAUGAAAGUCAAGCACUUGGCAUAUAGUAAAACCUCUGUAAAUGUUAGCUGCUGUUAUUUUUAUUAACUCCUCCUGUAUAUGUAAGUGUACAUGUAUUUCUCAGAAGCUAGUAAUAGUGCGGGCACGUGAAACAAUACAGCUUUCUUAAAUUUGCAGCUGAAACUUAGAAGGCACUUGGACAUUGUGUGUAAUUUUUUUCCAGUUGAGGUGUAACAUAGUAAUAUCACAAGUGUACAGCUAAUGUAUACUAAGUGAACAGCUAGAUGAAUUGUUACAUAUGCACAUGUCUGUGGUAACCAGUACCCAGAUGGAGAUAUAGAACAUUUCCUUGGCCUUAGAAAGCUCCCUGGUGCCCAUCCCAGGCAGCCCUCCCUCUUGCUAGCAGGCAGCAGCUAUUCUGAAGAGUUGGAAUAGAUGAGUUUUGCCUGUUCGUGAACUGUAUGAACAUGGACUCCUACAGUAUGUAGUCUUAUGUUGGAGUUCUUGCACUGCUCAAUAAUGAGCAUUGUAAUAGACAUAAGCCUGUGAGAUUUAUUCAUGUUAUUGAAUAACAUUUAUUUAUGUAUACAGUACUAAUUCAUGCUUUGUAAAUUGUUGUAGAGUCUUUUGUGCGGUUUGAAAUUCAUAAUAAUUCAUUUUAUUGGCACAUUGGAUACACAGUCUUUGGGGGAAAAAAGAAAAUAACACUUCUUCCUACAUUACUAGAAAAUCAGAUCCCAAUGGCUAUCUUAGGAAAACAACCAUGACCUCAUUUUUAUUCACAGAACUGGGUUUAUUCACUACUUGAAGGUAUAAUUACCUUCAGUUACAAUUCCAUAAACCAAAUACUUUGAAAACUGUAUUCAUUUUUAUGUGUGUGUUUUUAGGAGGGAGCCUCAAAAUAGGGGAAAAGGACCAUCUAAGGUAGCUUAUAUCCUUCAUGCUUAGGACUAAAUGCCGUAAUCAACACUUAGCGUUGUACAGAAGUAACCACCAGUCCAGCAUUAGUAUAAUAUUCUUUGAGUUUAAAAUGAAACAGUACAAUGCUUUUCUGAAGAAAAAAGAAAAGUCCACCAUAAAAGGAAGAAAGUGGAGCUAGGAUGUUAUACUGCAGGAAGAUUUUGAGGAACAGGACCAAGCACUUAUAUCAGGAAGAAGAGUUUUGGCCACUAACCUAUUAACAAUUGUGGUCAGGCUAUGCCUAUACAUUCAGAAUUUGUUUGUAUUGUUGAAAUUCUCUAAUAUGCUAAAUAAAAUUUAUUUCACAGACAGACAAGAUGAUUCAGUAGAUGAAAUCAGAAGGGUUUUUGUUUGUUUGUUUUAAAUUUUGGAAGGGACUUUGGCUGUGGUUAAUAGCUUGUAUUUCUGUUAUUGGAAAUGUUGAUUAAGGAUUUUGUGGGUGUUCUGCUUGAACACUAGCCAUUUUUCUCUCAGGAGACAUUGUAUUUUUCAACAUUUAUAAUUUUAUUAAAUCUGACUAUUCAUAGCUCUUGACACAAGGUCAUUCUUCACAUACAGCCAUAUGCAGGAUGGGUUCCUCUGGACUGGAGAAGGGCAAAUUGUCCCCUUUUCUUCCUAAAUCAGACCAUCCGUGGUCAGGAUUUCAUUGGGGGUUGGGAGCGUUGAAAUAGUGAUACAUGAUUCAUCUUUUGAUCUAUAGGCGUCCUCAAAGAUGCAGAUUAUGUUUCAGAAGAAAGAAGAACUAUCCAACAAAUAGAGCUGCCUCAUGUGAAGCAGUGCUGUUUGGAAGGGGCAUGGACUCCUGAUUCCUGGAAGUGUUGUAAUGGCAUUUGCAAAGGCUGCUGUGGGAAGAAUCUCUUUCUUGGGUGCAACAUUGAACCAAAUAACCUCUAAGGCAUUUGUAGGACUGAGGUUCCAUGAAAUAGGCUUUUAUGGUAUGCCUAGGCUACAUACCCACCACGUACAUGAUUUUGGAGUGAACCAAGGACUGGGUUUUGCUCUGGAAGCCUGUCCUGAUUGCUUCUGUAAUCUGGCGCUAUGCAUCCGGAUCUUGGACCCUUAUGUACACUGCUGUAUGUUACUCUUACAAUUCUGUGCUCUUCUGUGAGUUCAGACUUGGCACCUUAUUUUACUUCUGAGCCGCUCUCUGCUGUCCAGAAACUUGGUGGACCUGUAGUACUGCAUUGUUCUGCUCAACCUGUGACCACUCGUAUCUCAUGGCUGCAUAACGGAAAAACAUUGGAUGGAAACCUGGAACAUGUUAAGAUUCAUCAGGGGACUCUGACAAUUCUUUCUCUCAACUCCUCUCUUUUGGGUUACUACCAGUGCCUUGCCAACAAUAGCAUCGGUGCCAUUGUGAGUGGCCCUGCGACAGUAUCUGUGGCAGUUCUUGGUGAUUUUGGUUCAUCCACAAAGCAUGUUAUUACAGCAGAAGAAAAAAGUGCUGGUUUCAUUGGCUGCAGGGUACCGGAGAGUAACCCCAAAGCUGAGGUGCGCUAUAAAAUCCGGGGAAAAUGGCUGGAACAUUCCACAGAGAAUUACUUAAUCCUUCCAUCAGGAAAUCUUCAGAUUUUGAAUGUAUCCUUAGAGGACAAGGGAUCAUACAAAUGUGCAGCUUAUAAUCCUGUCACACAUCAAUUAAAAGUUGAACCUAUUGGCCGAAAGCUCCUUGUGAGUCGUCCUUCUUCAGAUGAUGUUCACAUUCUUCACCCCACCCAUUCACAGGCAUUAGCUGUUCUUUCUCGUAGCCCUGUAACCUUGGAGUGUGUGGUGAGUGGGGUCCCGGCUCCUCAAGUGUAUUGGCUAAAGGACGGGCAGGACAUUGCACCAGGAAGCAACUGGAGAAGGUUGUAUUCUCAUCUUGCCACUGAUAGCGUUGACCCGGCGGACUCCGGAAACUAUUCCUGCAUGGCGGGAAACAAGUCUGGAGAUGUAAAAUAUGUGACUUACAUGGUUAAUGUACUUGAACAUGCUUCCAUUUCUAAAGGACUACAGGAUCAGAUAGUGUCUCUGGGUGCCACAGUACACUUUACCUGCGACGUUCAUGGGAACCCAGCCCCCAACUGUACCUGGUUUCACAAUGCACAGCCUAUUCAUCCUUCUGCACGACAUCUAACUGCAGGAAACGGACUGAAAAUCAGUGGGGUUACUGUGGAAGAUGUUGGGAUGUAUCAGUGUGUAGCAGAUAAUGGGAUUGGAUUUAUGCACUCUACUGGAAGACUUGAAAUUGAAAAUGACGGUGGAUUCAAGCCAGUUAUAAUUACGGCACCAGUAAGUGCAAAGGUUGCAGACGGAGACUUUGUUACUCUGUCCUGCAAUGCCAGUGGGCUGCCGGUUCCGGUCAUUCGUUGGUAUGACAGCCAUGGAUUGAUAACCAGCCAUCCAUCUCAAGUCCUGAGAUCGAAAUCCCGAAAAUCACAGUUAUCAAGACCUGAGGGCUUGAACCUGGAGCCUGUGUACUUCGUCCUGUCCCAAGCUGGUGCAAGCUCUCUCCAUAUUCAGGCUGUGACUCAGGAACAUGCGGGGAAAUACAUCUGCGAAGCUGCAAAUGAACAUGGUACCACACAGGCAGAAGCAUCUCUCAUGGUUGUUCCUUUUGAAACAAAUACAAAAGCAGAGACAGUCACACUUCCUGAUGCUGCUCAGAAUGAUGACAGAAGUAAGAGAGAUGGUUCAGAAACUGGGUUACUGAGCUCAUUUCCGGUGAAGGUCCAUCCCAGUGCAGUGGAAUCAGCACCAGAGAAAAACGCCAGCGGCAUCUCUGUUCCUGAUGCCCCCAUCAUACUGAGCCCCCCACAGACCCACACACCAGACACGUACAACCUGGUGUGGAGGGCAGGCAAGGAUGGUGGGCUGCCCAUCAAUGCUUACUUUGUGAAGUAUCGAAAGCUGGAUGAUGGGGUUGGCAUGCUGGGAAGCUGGCACACGGUUCGAGUCCCAGGAAGUGAAAAUGAGCUCCAUUUAGCUGAGCUGGAGCCAUCUAGUCUUUAUGAAGUCUUGAUGGUAGCAAGAAGCGCAGCAGGUGAAGGCCAACCUGCCAUGCUUACCUUCCGAACCAGCAAAGAAAAAACAGCGUCAUCAAAAAACACCCAGGCAUCCUCUCCACCCGUGGGCAUCCCUAAGUAUCCCGUUGUUUCAGAGGCUGCAAACAACAAUUUUGGAGUGGUACUUACAGAUUCCUCUAGGCACAGUGGAGUUCCAGAGGCACCAGAUCGGCCUACCAUCUCCACUGCAUCAGAGACAUCAGUCUAUGUCACUUGGAUUCCUCGGGCAAACGGGGGUUCUCCAAUCACUGCCUUCAAAGUCGAAUAUAAACGGAUGAGGACCAGCAAUUGGCUGGUGGCAGCUGAAGACAUCCCUCCUUCCAAACUUUCAGUGGAAGUUCGUAGUUUAGAACCAGGUUCAACAUACAAAUUUAGGGUCAUUGCCAUCAACCAUUAUGGUGAGAGUUUUCGGAGUUCAGCAUCUCGUCCUUAUCAAGUGGUUGGGUUCCCCAAUCGCUUUUCCAGCCGUCCAAUAACUGGACCUCACAUUGCAUACACAGAGGCUGUCAGCGAUACUCAGAUCAUGCUAAAGUGGACGUACAUUCCAUCAAGUAACAAUAACACUCCCAUUCAAGGAUUUUAUAUCUAUUACCGACCAACAGAUAGUGACAAUGACAGUGAUUACAAGAGGGAUGUUGUAGAAGGUUCAAAGCAGUGGCACAUGAUUGGCCACCUGCAGCCAGAAACCUCCUAUGACAUUAAAAUGCAAUGCUUCAAUGAAGGAGGAGAAAGUGAAUUUAGCAAUGUGAUGAUCUGCGAGACUAAAGUGAAACGUGUUCCUGGAGCUUCUGAAUAUCCUGUCAAAGACUUGAGUACCCCUCCAAAUUCUUUGGGAAGUGGAGGAAAUGUGGGGCCUGCAACCAGCCCUGCCAGAAGCAGUGACAUGUUAUAUCUGAUCGUUGGCUGUGUGCUGGGCGUCAUGGUCCUCAUUCUGAUGGUUUUCAUUGCAAUGUGCCUGUGGAAGAAUCGCCAGCAGAAUACCAUACAAAAAUAUGACCCACCAGGAUAUCUCUACCAAGGAUCAGAUAUGAACGGGCAGAUGGUGGACUACACCACUCUCUCAGGAGCAAGUCAGAUAAAUGGAAAUGUUCACGGAGGCUUCCUAACCAAUGGCGGUCUCAGCAGUGGCUAUUCCCACCUUCACCAUAAGGUCCCCAAUGCAGUCAAUGGAAUUGUGAAUGGGAGCCUAAAUGGAGGGCUUUACUCCGGGCACAGCAACUCUCUAACCAGGACACACGUGGAUUUUGAACAUCCUCAUCAUCUAGUGAAUGGUGGUGGAAUGUACACGGCCGUGCCUCAGAUUGACCCUCUGGAGUGUGUUAACUGCCGAAAUUGUCGAAACAACAAUAGGUGUUUCACCAAAACCAACAGCACUUUCAGCAGCAGCCCUCCUCCUGUGGUCCCUGUGGUAGCACCUUAUCCUCAGGAUGGUUUGGAAAUGAAGCCCCUCAGUCACGUGAAGGUGCCUGUAUGCCUGACUUCCGCAGUCCCUGAUUGUGGCCAGUUGCCGGAGGAGAGCGUCAAGGACAAUGUGGAACCAGUCCCUACUCAGCGUACCUGCUGUCAGGACAUUGUAAAUGACGUCAGCUCUGAUGGCUCAGAAGAUCCAGCAGAGUUCAGCAGAGGUCAGGAAGGCAUGAUCAACCUUAGGAUUCCAGAUCAUCUUCAGUUAGCUAAGAGCUGUGUAUGGGAAGGAGACAGCUGUGCCCAUUCAGAAACAGAGAUCAACAUUGUAAGUUGGAAUGCUCUUAUUUUGCCACCUGUCCCCGAGGGCUGUGCUGAGAAGACAAUGUGGUCUCCACCUGGCAUUCCUUUAGACAGCCCGACAGAGGUCCUUCAGCAGCCCCGGGAAACCUGAGGACAUGCAAACAACCAGUCAUGUUCCAACUUCAAGCCGGUAACUGCACACAACAGGCCUGGGAGCGAACUGUGUGAAGGACCUUAAUUCAAAUCAGAGAAAAUCAUUAUUUAUUUUUUUGUAGUAGUAAUGUCAUAUGAAUGUAUCUUAAAACGUGUGCCCUUUUAUAUUAUUUAUGCCUUAAAUGUUUUCUUCCCCAUUCCUUCCUCCCCCUCGGUAGGAAACAACCUUGUUUUGCAUAGUAUUCAGUCACCUGGAGGGCAGAGGGGUCCUUCCAUGUUUUCUAACAGCUAUAGUGACAGCAAGAGCUCCUCAUGCAAAGGAUCCCAUCUCUUGGCUGCUUCGGCUAGGAGGGAAUGCAGGGGCCCGUUGAAGGUUGCCACCAGCUGGGUUUUCAGGUGGAAAAUGGUCUUUCAAUAGUGUAUUCUCAGACUUUUUUUUGUUUGUUUUUUGAGAUGGAGUCUUGCUGUCAUCCAGGCUGGAGUGCAAUGGCUCGAUCUUGGCUCACUGCAACCUCCGCCUCCCAGGUUCAAGCAAUUCUCCCGCCUCAGCCUCCUGAGUAGCUGGGACUACAGGCACCUGCCACCACGUCCAGCUAAUUGUCUUGUAUUUUUAUUAGAGACAAGGUUUCAGGCUGGUUUUGAACUCCUGACCUCAAGUGAUCCACCCGCCUCCGCCUCCCAAAGUGCGAGGAUUACAGGCGUGAGCCACCACGUCUGGCCUGUAUUAUCAGACUUCCUGAGAACACUUUGAAAUCAACUGCAGUUGUGACCCAUGUUUAUAAUAACAGACCUGGCUGACGGAUUUUACAAGAGUGCCUUCCACAGAAGUGGUAAUGUGACCUGUUGACUUUGUAUCUGCACGUGGGCACGAGUGAUGUUCAGUUUGCUAGGCACUAGUCAUAGUGUUAUGGACGUGGUGGAGUGUAAGGUCUUGAUGAAUUACGGCAGUAUGCAGAAAAGGAACCAAGGCCAGAGAGACAAAUAAUGCCUCAUGUCCCACUGCUUUAAAAUUACAUUAAUUUAUAAAAUGGCCACUAUGGGCUCUUUUUGACUGUUUCUCGGAGUAGGAACAAAAUAAGACAUUAAAUGGUGGCUUGAAGAGAAAGAUACACAUUUUCAGAAGAAAGAAAGGGGAGGGCUGCAGGGAGCCUGUCUUGGCGGGAGCUCUCCAGUCUGUUGGAUUAGCACAGGGACACGCUUAUGGUGCCAUGACGCCGAAACUAGUCAUCCCCCAUCUCCAGCAUAGGCAACGGCCUGCAGGGGUGAGUGUCAGAAAAGACUUACUUUGGAAGAAAAGGGUUUUUUUUUGUUUGUUUGUUUUUUGUUUUUUUUUGUUUGUUUGUUUUGGGUUUUUUUCCUGAAAUUUCCUGAUACCUUUUUCAGAAUGUCACCCUUGUAAAUAGGCACCUAAAGCCAAGUUGGUCAGCAGAGCUCCUGACCACGGCUGCCUCUGCGUGACAAGGACAUUUGCAGCUGCCUUUGGAAGGCUCUUCACAUUAAAAAACAAUAAUUAUGUAAGUGUGUUUCAUAGCUUGAGUCAAGCUUUCAAGGAUCACUGCUCCUUUGUGCAUUGUGCAUCCCUUUGGGGAAAGAAACAGAAAAUUAUUCUCUUUCUAUAGAGUCAAGCAAUUCCAGCAGAAGUGAAGAAAUGUUAGUUUCCCAGAAAUCGCAGUGGAAUAGAAUACAAUACUGUGUUAACCAACUUUCUGUAUAAAUGCAUCAGUAUUCCCUUACAUAUGUCUAUAUAUUUUAUAAUAGAACUGUUAGUGAAAAUGUGCUUGUUUAAGCUGGGUCACUAUGCAAGAGUUACUUCCAGUAGAAUGUAGUGAAUGUAAUUCCCUAGUCGGAUAUUAGGGAUGCUGUAGACCCAAGUUCUACAUUCCAGAUGUCCGUGCCUAUAGUAUACUGGAUUUAUUCUUCAUGUUGCUUAAAUGCAGUUAGCUCUGGAGGGGGAUAGCUGCAUCCCUUACUUCUGUGACUAGCAAAGGACAAAGUCCCAGCGCACAGAAUAUGAAAACAUACCCUGUGUUAGCCAAUCAAGUUACAGCAAUGCUGUCACAAAGGGAGUUUUAGAAAACUGGGGAGUCAUUGUCCGUAGACAGCCAUUUUGAUUUAGGAAACAGGUGUAUUAGCAUGAGCCUUAGGUCAUGAACUGCUUUUAAAGAUUGAGUUUGAAUAUGGGAUCUGUCCACGAGGAAGAGAAAAUGGCUUUACCUUUAGGACAAUCUCAUUGUGGACUGCUUUAUUUAUAUUAUUAGUAACGCUGUUUUAAGUGUUAUUCUUUUUAUUGUAUUUUAUUUAUAAAAAAUGCCUUUAUAUAUUGAAAUAUAUAAAUAUAUAUAUAUAAACACACACACACACACACACACACACAUAUAUAUAUAUAUAUAUAAUUGCCUUUAUAUUUAGGCGGUAUGAGUUCUCCCUAAGCGUGAGUUGGCUCUGCCCUGCACAGGCACCCAAACAGUCCUACCUAAUGUCACUUCACCAGGAAAUGAGAGGACAUGGUACAGUGUGGGAGACAGCACUAACACGUGCUGAAUAACUACUGUGUACCAGGCACUGUGCUCGGUGCUUGUUACUGUUAACUCAUUUAACCCCCACAACUCAUCUACAAAGUUGGCAUUAAAAUCCCCAAGUCACUCAGUGAGCCAUGGGACCUGAAUCCGAACCUAGUUUAUCUGGAGCCAUAAUCUGGGCUCCUCCCAUUUUUCCAUACUGCUUUCCAAAAGCAUUGUGGUUCACUCUUUGGAUGGAACCAGUCCCGUUCCGUAUGCUGUGAUCUAUCCCUGCCGUGGAAUUCCUCCGAGGCUCCAACUCCGCAGCCAGAGAAGCUGCUCUCUGGCCUCCGCGGGCAGAGCUCUGCUUAUGACUUCGUCUUCCAGAGGUCCACAUUUCUCCCCUUGACGCCCCCUGUCUACCACCUCCACCUGGAAAUUUGAUCUUUACUGUGCUCAGUGAUCACGAAAUUGGUCAAGCCUAUUCAUGUUCCUUCUCAUCUAGAAUUCUGUGUGAUUGUUUUAGCAUAAACUGCCCCGCUCCCACUGUAUCAUUUCACGAUCUCCUUUUAAUGUUUUUCUUUCAGUUUUGCACUGACAGUCUGGUGACAGGUGCUGCCAGGGUGCAAGUUACAUUGCAAUGUUCUAAACCUUUUGAAGUGUUCUUAGCAAAAGCCUUUCUUUCUGGGUGUUUUUGUCGAAUGAGUCUAUGAAGACUCAAUGCAUCCAUCUUGGGCUGAUCAUGCCACAGAUCUCAUUCCAGCUAUAGUACUGCCAAGAAGUGAAGUUUAUCAUUGAAUUUUACCUGUGUUGCUCUCUUUUAAAGUAAUGACUUUGAGAUGCAUGCUUUGUAUCAUAUUGAAAAGUAUGUUUUAUUUUCCUUAAAGUUGUAAUAUUGUGUGUGAAACUGUACAUAUUUUAAAUGAUGUAGCUUUGGCAGGUUUUAUUUGGUUGAUAUGAUUUUAUAUUAAAAGAGAAGGCUGCUUUCAUAUAGCAUAGCCCCUGAAGGUGGGAAUACUCCCUGUUUGUACAACGCUGCUUAUAGUUUGUGAUUGGGGUGGGCGAAUGUCUUCCUCUGAAAUUCUUUGGAACCCCCCACCCCUGUCCUCCCCUGAAACUCCCCUGUGCACACCCCUCUGUUCUGACUGCAGAGAUCAAGGCCCUGAAGGAGCAGGAUCUUGGGCAAGUGUUUUAGGGGACGCUGAGAACAUACCUGACCCUGGGGGCGAUGUGGAGGCAGGCCCACCUCCUCGGGGCAACUUUGCGUUUCCUUGGAGGGAAGGGAGGUGGGUAGGAGAGGAGCUUGGGAGGAUGAGGAGGAGCGGUCCCGCCUCACACAUUGUCUAUUUUUACCAUUAACCGAGCGCCACAUGUUUAUGAACUUCAGGAUAGAAAUUUAGCCUCCUUGUGAAAACGUUUUGUUUUACUGCCCUAAGAAAAUACACAUCUCUAGGCUUGUCUGACCAGAAAGCCAGCAAAGUCUUUUGCAUCGGGUGUGGCCCUUUUGUAUUUUAUUUCCCAUAUUUAAAUAAGCCUUCCUUAAACCCUAGCCCCAGUCCUGAGAGCUUUGAGGGUAGCCGAAACCCCUUAUCUAAUAAAGUCUAACUCUGUGAGAACCACA